GUCAUUCCAAGCUCUCCUGCGUCAGCUUGUGUAGCUGGUUAGUACUGGCUUAGAGGAAAAAGAAAACGAGUCACUUCCUGAGCACACUGGAGUCUGGAAGCUUAGAGGAAAAGGAGGAGGAGCAACUUCAUUAGCACAGUGGAGGCUGGAGCCUGCCGUGGCUCACCUCGCUGCUGCCGUUGGUGCGGGCCAGGGAGACUAGAGCGCAGCCAGAAUGGCUUUCUUGGCUUUGCCUGCCCAGUUGUUUCAUGCCAGGAGGAGGAGCCGCCUGCUGGAGGCUGGAGCUUGUGGCACCACCGCUCGCCUCGCUGUGGUUGGUGGCGGCCAUGGAGACUAAAGACUCAGCGCUGGAGUGGUAGGAGGGCGGCAAUGAAAACUGAAGAGCACCAGAGCGGUGGCGCUGUGUGGAAGUUUAUGAAGAGACCUGGUCCGGAUCCAAGCUUUCUGUCCCCGUUCUACUUUCUGAAACGCCCACCAAAAGACACGGGCCCCUGGCAUCUCAUAACCACUCAGCGAUGCUGAAGACCAACCGAGGUACUAUAGGAGGCUUCUUCCUCGCUGGUCGUGAUAUGGCCUGGUGGCCGAUGGGCGCCUCUCUCUUUGCCAGUAACAUCGGCAGCAACCACUAUGUGGGGCUGGCUGGGACAGGAGCAGCUUCAGGAGUCGCCACCGUAACAUUUGAAUGGACUUCCUCAGUAAUGUUGCUGAUUCUUGGGUGGAUCUUUGUCCCUAUCUACAUCAAGUCGGGGGUGAUGACCAUGCCGGAAUAUCUCAAGAAGCGGUUUGGUGGGGAGCGACUCCAGGUCUACCUCUCCAUCCUCUCCCUCUUCAUCUGUGUGGUUUUGUUAAUUUCUGCAGACAUAUUUGCUGGAGCCAUAUUCAUCAAGCUGGCCUUGGGAUUGGACCUUUACCUGGCAAUCUUCAUCCUCUUGGCUAUGACUGCUGUUUACACCACCACUGGGGGCUUGGCCUCGGUGAUUUACACAGACACCCUCCAGACCAUCAUCAUGCUGAUUGGCUCUUUUAUUCUCAUGGGGUUUGCAUUUAACGAAGUUGGAGGUUAUGAGAGCUUUACCGAGAAGUACGUGAAUGCCACCCCAUCCGUAGUCGAGGGGGACAACUUGACAAUCAGUGCCAGUUGCUACACACCUCGGGCGGACUCCUUCCACAUCUUCCGAGAUGCUGUGACUGGGGACAUUCCAUGGCCAGGAAUUAUAUUUGGAAUGCCCAUUACAGCUUUGUGGUACUGGUGCACAAAUCAGGUCAUUGUGCAGCGCUGCCUGUGUGGCAAGGACAUGUCUCACGUGAAGGCCGCUUGCAUUAUGUGUGCUUACCUGAAGCUGCUGCCCAUGUUCCUCAUGGUGAUGCCGGGGAUGAUCAGCCGCAUCCUGUACACAGAUAUGGUAGCAUGUGUGGUACCUUCUGAAUGCGUGAAACACUGUGGCGUUGAUGUUGGCUGCACCAACUACGCAUACCCCACGAUGGUGCUGGAACUGAUGCCCCAAGGACUGCGAGGCCUGAUGCUUUCGGUCAUGCUGGCCUCUCUCAUGAGCUCCCUGACCUCCAUCUUCAACAGCGCCAGCACCCUCUUCACCAUUGACCUCUACACCAAGAUGCGGAAGCAAGCGUCGGAGAAAGAGCUCCUGAUAGCUGGACGGAUAUUUGUUCUUCUAUUAACUGUUGUGAGCAUUGUGUGGGUCCCACUGGUACAAGUUUCUCAAAAUGGACAACUAAUCCAUUACACAGAAUCAAUUUCUAGCUACCUUGGGCCUCCAAUUGCAGCUGUCUUUGUGCUUGCCAUCUUCUGUAAAAGAGUCAAUGAACAGGGAGCAUUCUGGGGUCUAAUGGUUGGACUUGCAAUGGGCCUCAUUCGUAUGAUAACAGAGUUUGCUUAUGGAACAGGGAGUUGCUUGGCUCCCAGUAACUGUCCCAAGAUUAUCUGUGGAGUGCACUAUCUGUACUUUUCCAUCGUUCUCUUUUUUGGGUCCAUGCUGGUCACCCUGGGAAUUUCCCUCUUAACAAAACCCAUUCCUGAUGUACAUCUGUACCGCCUGUGCUGGGUUCUUCGGAACAGUACAGAGGAGCGAAUCGAUAUAGAUGCAGAAGAGAAAAGUCAGGAAGAAACAGAUGAUGGUGUUGAAGAAGAUUAUCCUGAGAAAUCACGUGGAUGCCUCAAGAAAGCUUAUGACUUGUUCUGCGGUUUGCAGAAGGGACCCAAGCUAACCAAGGAGGAGGAGGAAGCCUUGAGCAAGAAGCUCACAGACACGUCUGAGAGGCCCUCGUGGAGGACAAUAGUGAACAUCAACGCCAUCCUCCUCCUGGCUGUGGUGGUCUUUAUUCACGGCUACUAUGCCUGAACUCUAUCUGAGCCAUUAGAAUAAUGAAUAAUUCUUAAUAAUGAACCAAA